CUUCUCAGCAUGGACCGCACUUGUGAGGAGAGGCCCGCUGAGGAUGGGAGCGACGAGGAGGACCCAGACUCCAUGGAAGCCCCAACCCGGAUCCGGGACACUCCGGAAGACAUCGUGCUGGAAGCUCCGGCUAGUGGGCUGGCGUUCCAUCCGGCCCGUGACCUACUGGCUGCAGGGGACGUGGACGGGGACGUGUUCGUGGGGAAUUAUACCUACCCUUGCAGAGGGGACAAGUUUGCAGUACAGCACCUAAGCAGCUCUUCAACAAAUCUUUUCCUACUCUUGCCAAGAGGGAGAAACCAAGGAGCUCUGGUCAUCAGGUCACCAUCUCAAGGCCUGCCGAGCUGUGGCCUUCUCUGAAGAUGGGCAGAAGCUCAUUACUGUCUCCAAGGACAAAGCCAUCCAUGUUCUAGAUGUGGAGCAGGGCCAACUGGAAAGACGUGUUUCCAAGGCUCAUGGUGCCCCCAUCAAUAGUCUUCUGCUGGUGGAUGAGAAUGUUCUGGCCACUGGGGAUGACACAGGUGGUAUCUGUCUCUGGGACCAGCGGAAGGAGGGCCCCUUAAUGGAUAUGAGGCAACAUGAAGAGUACAUCGCAGACAUGGCUCUGGAUCCAGCCAAAAAGCUGCUGCUGACAGCCAGCGGGGAUGGCUGCCUUGGCAUCUUCAACAUUAAGAGGCGUCGGUUUGAGCUGCUCUCAGAACCUCAGUCUGGGGACCUGACCUCUGUCACUCUCAUGAAAUGGGGGAAGAAGGUAGCCUGUGGCUCCAGUGAAGGUACCAUCUACCUCUUCAAUUGGAAUGGCUUUGGGGCCACAAGUGACCGCUUUGCCCUGAGAGCUGAAUCUAUCGACUGCAUGGUUCCAGUCACCGAGAGUCUGCUGUGUACUGGCUCCACUGAUGGAGUCAUCAGGGCUGUGAACAUCCUACCGAACCGAGUGGUGGGCAGUGUGGGCCAGCACACUGGGGAGCCUGUGGAGGAGCUGGCCCUCUCCCACUGUGGCCGCUUCCUGGCCAGUAGUGGCCAUGACCAGCGCCUCAAGUUUUGGGACAUGGCCCAGCUGCGAGCUGUGGUGGUGGAUGACUACCGUCGGCGCAAAAAAAAGGGAGGACCACUGCGGGCUCUGAGCAGCAAGACUUGGAGCACCGAUGACUUCUUCGCAGGACUGAGGGAAGAGGGAGAAGACUCCAUGGCUCAGGAAGAAAAGGAGGAGACUGGGGAUGACAGUGACUGAAGGAAUGAAUUGAAUCUUGAGACGGGUCCUCACCAGGCAAGAGUCUUGCUUAUUGGGCUGCAUCCCCAGAGAGGAUAUGAAUUAUUUUUUGAAAAGACAGGGUUUUGCCAUCGUCCAGGCUGGAGUGCGCUGGCUUGAUCUUGGCUCACUGCAGCCUCAAUGUCCCCAGGCUCAGAUUGUCCUUCCACCUUAGCCUCUGGAGCAGCUGGGACUACAGGUGUGCACUACCACACCAGGCCAAUUUUUGUUUUUUUUUUUUGGUAGAAACGGGUCUGUUUUGCCCAGGCUGGUCUUCAACUCCUGGACUCAAAUGAUCCACCUGCCUCUGCUUCCCAAAGUGCUGGGAUUACAGGCACGAGCCACCACACCUGGCCAAAAAAAUUUAUAUUUUUUGAGACAAGGUCUCACUCUGUCACCCAGGCUGGAGUACAGUGGGUUGAUCAUGGCUCACUGCAUCCUUGACUUCCUGGGCUCAAGUGAUCCACCUCAGCCUGCCUGGUAGCUGAGACUUAACAGGCAUCUGCCACCAUGCUUGACUAAUUUUUGUGAUUUUUUUUUGGUAGAGACCAGGGGUUUCACUAUGUUGACCAAGCUGGUCUUGGAACUCCUGGGCUCAAGUGAUCCUCCUGCCUUGGCCUCCCAAAAUGCUGGGAUUACAGGCAUGAGCCACUGUGCCUGGCUGGAUAUGAAAUUUUUUUUUUUUUUUUUUUUGAGACAGGGUUUCGCUCUUGUUGCCAGGGCUGGAGUGCAAUGGCGUGAUCUUGGCUCACUGCAACCUCCGCCUCCCGGGUUCAAGCAAUUCUCCUGCCUCAGCCUCCCAAGUAGCUGGGAUUACAGGUGUCUGCCACCAUGCCAGGCUAAUUUUUGUAUUUUCAGUAGAGACGGGGUUUCUCCAUGCUGGCCAGGCUGGUCUCGAACUCCUGACCUCAGGUGAUCCACCCGCCUCAGCCUCCCAAAGUGCUGGGAUUACAGGCAAAAGCCAACACACCCGGCCUGGAUAUGAAUUUAUAAUACCCUACAGUGCAACACAAGAAGAUGCACUCAAAGCACUGAUGUGAGGAAGUACUUGCCCCGUAGCAGCUAUUCACUCUACCAGUGUAAACAAACUCUAAGCUAGGGCAAGACAGCACAGACACAAGUAUAUACUAACCAGGGGUUUAAUAUAAAUACAACCAGCAUAGAAAGACCCAAAACUAUACAGAAACCAAAACCAGAAUGCCAUGUGGUGGAGGCAAAGGGCAGAAUUUCUGACCCCUUUGGCUCAGCUGCCCUUCCCCACAAAUAAAAACCAACAAAGAGGACAAAUCAGGACAAUAAAGAAGAUUCAUGCUAAGCUGUGGCAGAGGGGGGAAGGUAUGAUCGGGUGGGGGUGGGACAAGGAACGGCCAUGGAAGAUCACUGGGUCAGGUUGGACCCUGGGCUGGGAGCGGGAGGGCAAGGCCCCUCACCACAACUUAACCCAAACCUAAGCUGCCCCCAGGUGCCAUAGGUCCCUGUCCCAGCAGGGAGGCUGAUGGGCCUGGGCCCAUGCCCCUCCCCACCUUUGGGGGUCAGAAAGUGGCCACCCAGGCCUGCUGGGAUGGGGCCUGACACAGGCUCUGCAUGCCCAUUCAGGGUGCCUGUGGAGAAAGAAUGGAGUCACUGUUUAACCAUGGUACCUGCCUCAGCCCCAGCAGACCACAGGAGGUUGGCCCCAGACUCACUGAGUGCCUGCAGCAGCCGUACAGACACAGCAUCCUUGGCCACCUCAUGCCCAUCCCGGCCAUCUAGGGUCAGCACAACCCAGAUGAGGCCGCUGAAGGGCACCGGAUGCCCAGGAAUCACCACCUGGUACCAGAAGCGGUGCCAGCCAGCAGGUCCUAUGCCCAAACACUUGGUGAGGAACACAGGGCUGCCCAGCUUCAUUCGUUGGCACAGCAACUGCAGGGUAGCCCGAGCCCCUUGGAACCCUAACUUGUCCCUUGCCAAAGCCAACUGGCUGCCCUCUGGCUGUGGGGACCGCAAGAAGGGACCCACAAGCUGCUGGCGAAGUCGCUGCUUCAGGUCUGGCUUGAGCCACUCCACAGCCACCUGCUCUCCACAGAGGUGUGACUGCCCUGUAGGAAAAAUGCAAAGACAAGGGCAGGUCUAAACCCUGGGCCCAAGCCUCCAGGUGGUGAGCCCUUUGGAGCUACACAGUCCUGUUAUUUGUAGCCUUCCCAUUUCCUGGUAGUGUGACCAUGGGUAAGAAAAGACAAUGAAGCCUUCAGCCUCCAUUAUUUGCAAAGGGAGUAUAACACACUGCUACCUUACAAGUUUCCUUGGAGAAGUACUGGUUAAUUGCAGGCUUUGUCUGCCUCAUAACCAUCAUAAUGGCUAAUCUUUACUGGGAAAACUUGCUGUAAGUCAGUCAGUGUGCUAAGUACCGUACACCCAUUAUGUUACUUAAUUCUCAUAACAGUCUGAGGAAACAGAUUCUAUAGUAGUAAAAAGCUCAGUUGGAUUCCCUUGAGCAAAUCAAUUUCUCUAACAGUUUCCUCAUAGCUUGAGGGUCCUGUGCCUAUUUUGCGGUGUGGGGGUGGGGGAAGGUUGAGAAUUAAGUCAGGAGGUAAUGCUCGGGAAGUGUCACAAAUUUAGGUAAGCGGUGGUGGUAGCACCAUUGGAAGUUUUAAAAAUCUGAGAUCAAAUAGUAAAAGGUUGCAAAUUCUGGCA